AGGGGAGCACCAACAGGUGCUGCAGGCCGUGGAGCUCCAGGGCUUGGGCCUCUCGUUCAGCGCCUGCUCCCUGGCCCUGGACCAGGCCCAGCUUACACCCCUGCUGCGGGCCCUCAAGCUGCACACAGCACUCCGGGAGCUGCGCCUGGCAGGGAACCGGCUGGGGGACAAGUGUGUGGCUGAGCUGGUGGCUGCCCUGGGCACCAUGCCCAGCCUGGCCCUCCUUGACCUCUCCUCCAAUCACCUGGGUCCCGAAGGCCUGCGCCAGCUUGCCAUGGGGCUCCCAGGCCAAGCCACCUUGCAGAGUUUGGAGGAGCUGGACUUAAGCAUGAACCCCCUGGGGGACGGCUGUGGCCAGUCCCUGGCCUCCCUCCUGCACGCCUGCCCCUUACUCAGCACCCUGCGCCUGCAGGCGUGUGGCUUCGGCCCCAGCUUCUUUCUGAGCCACCAGACAGCACUGGGUAGUGCUUUCCAAGAUGCUGAGCACCUGAAGACCCUGUCCCUGUCCUACAACGCCCUGGGAGCCCCUGCCCUGGCCAGGACCCUGCAGAGCCUGCCCGCCGGCACCCUCCUGCACUUAGAGCUCAGCUCCGUGGCAGCCGGCAAGGGUGAUUCGGACCUCAUGGAGCCUGUAUUCCGAUACCUGGCCAAGGAAGGCUGUGCUCUAGCCCACCUGACCCUGUCUGCAAACCACCUGGGGGACAAGGCUGUUAGAGACCUGUGCAGAUGUCUCUCUCUGUGCCCCUCACUCAUCUCACUGGAUCUGUCUGCCAACCCUGAGAUCAGCUGUGCCAGCUUGGAAGAGCUCCUGUCCACCCUCCAAAAGCGGCCCCAAGGCCUUAGCUUCCUUGGCCUGUCAGGCUGCGCCGUCCAGGGUCCCCUGGGCCUGGGCCUGUGGGACAAGAUAGCCGCGCAGCUCCGGGAACUGCAGCUGUGCAGCAGACGCCUCUGCGCUGAGGACAGGGACGCCCUGCGCCAGCUGCAGCCCAGUCGGCCGGGCCCCGGCGAGUGCACGCUGGACCACGGCUCCAAGCUCUUCUUUCGGCGCCUCUGACCCUGGCGCUGCCUUUCCCCACCCUCACCGAAGCCCCUAAUAAAUGAAGCUGCUGGCCGGGCGCGGUGGCUCACGCCUGUAAUCCCAACACUUUGGGAGGCCCAGGCGGGCGGAUCACGAGGUCAGGAGAUCGAGACCAUCCUGGCUAACAUGGUGAAACCCCGUCUCUACUAAAAAUACCAAAAAUUAGCCGGGCGUGGUGGUGGAAGCCUGUAGUCCCAGCUACUCCGGAGGCUGAGGCAGGAGAAUGGCGUGAACCCGGGAGGCGGAGCUUGCAGUGAGCCGAGAUCGCACCACUGCACUCCAGCCUGGGCGACAGACCGAGACUCCGUCUCAAAAAAAAAAAAAAAUAAAAUAAAUGAAGCUGC